UGCAGAAGGCCCAGAUCUUUCUGCUGCAGAAGAGAGAAAGUGCGCCUUGCUGGGAAGUAGGGGAGGCCCUUCACCGGGAUGGUUUUUAUGGGGCAAGGCAGGUUUAGGAAAAUGGUGGGGAGGAAAGAGGGGCCCGUGUAGCGGCUAAAGCAGGGUUACAGAAUGGGAGACGGCAUCUUCAUAAGCCUCGAGGAUGUCACGGUGAGGGAUAUGCGGAGAGCAGGAAUGCUGCAGAUAGAAGGAAAUAAUGAGGUUAAGGGCUUUUUCUUAAAAGGGAGUCUUUUUAAGGUACAAAAAUAGGAAGUUACACAUAAUUUGGUAGUUUCCCGCAGUCCAGUCUGCCAUGGUUAACUAAGUUCUUUCAAAUGUGACAUAGUAACCGAGGCAACCUGUUUACGGUAGUAGAUCCUAGCUGCCAACAUUUCUAAACCAUUACUGUCAACUAGCUUUUCUGCUUCGACAGCCACAAGGAGAUGAGUUUUUCUCAUUUCAGUUUUCUUUUCCCCCGCUAGCAGCUUGCCUCCGAAAAGAUUUUGAGGCUGAGUAGUAGUUUAGGAAAGAGUCGACUAAAUUUACGGAUGUUUUCCCCCAUACAUAAAUACCAAUUGAGUUUUGUACUCCAUUCCAUCAGAAAUAGACUGUUGAGAAUUAAUGGCCCAUAUUAUUGUGCUUCUGAAUGUGCCUGCAUGUUUUCUAAGUGGUGGUUUAUUGGACCAUAUAGGAAUUUAAAAGACUGAUGAGUAACACUUUCUUAAGGAUCUUCUAACAUUUUAAAAUGUAAGGUCUAAGAAAGACAUAAUUUAAGUUCUUUUAACAUUUAGUUUGUGGUCAUAAGUUGACCUUUAUGUGCUUUCUGAAUUGGAACUUAAAAUAAUCUUUAAUUCAUUAUUUUUUCUACUUCUAGGCCAGUUUUGAGUUUAAUAUUUAUAAAAGGUUAGAUAGUUAUAGAUAGGAUUAUUUUGCAGUUUUGAAACAACAUACAAAUUGUUAUAGAUUUCAGAGUAGGGCUAAUCACAGGAAAGACAAAAGUCAGAAUGCUUCAGGUAAGCCCCUUCUCAUUAUAUAAGAUCAGAGCUUGUAGGUACAAAAUAAGGCCAGUUGUUUCUUCAACUACAGUGGGUAGGGAUCGGGGAGGCAUGGGGAGCUGAGAGGGUUCCACCCUCCUAAGUAGCCUCCUACCUCACUUCGAAGUUGUAUUUGUUUAUAUUAGUCAGAAGUGGUUCAGCAGCUUUGGGAAAUGCAUGCAUUCUCUACCUCCUCACCAUCAAAAAUAUGUUAAACAUAGAAAAGACUUAUCUAUAUAUUCCAAAAUUUACAAAUAUGUAAUUUGAAGAAGGUAUACUAUAUGGGAAACUGAAAAUGCAUUAGUAGGACAAAUAUGUAAUGAUUGAGAAGUCUGAAAUGCAUUAGAACUAAUACAUAUAUUAAUCACAUUUUAAACAUUAUUUUUAGUUGAUCUAGUUAGUCCUUUGAAAUCAGUCAUAACUAGGUAAGAUGAAGAUAGCCUAUCUGAAAUAGAAUUGAAAAUUGAGGAAAAAGUAAUAGAAUAAGUUGUAAAAGACCCUCCUAGCAUCUUGGAGACAUCUAAUUUAACAAGAAGUUUGCCUGUUGACUUCUGGAUUAAUAGUGUGUUACAAAAAGCAGAUUGAGUAUUUUGCAUACAGAUUGUCUGAUACGCACUAUCUUAAACCAGAAGGUGAUUUCAGAGAUGUUUAUAGGCAUAUCAUGCAUUUUUAAACAGAUCUUCAAGAGUUUCUUCAGUAGUAGACCACAGGAUUUUUAGUUUUCUAACUUAACCAAGCUCCUUUCUCUUAUUUUGUGCUAUUUAAUAGAAUAAUUUCAAUAGGCACGUCUUUAUUGAUUGCUGUUUAUCUUGUUUUACAUACACAGAUCUUUGAACUCUGGAACCAAAAGCCUUUAUGGUUACAAAUUAGAUAGAGAGACACAUCUCAAUUCAAAGGCAGCUUGCUGAUCUAGAGAAUUUAGCUUUUGUAACUGAUGGAAAUUUUGACUCUGCCAGCUCAUUGAACUCAGAUAAUCUUGAUGCAGGCAACAGACAGGCUUGUCCAUUGUGCCCUAAGGAAAAAUUCAGAGCUUGUAAUAGCCAUAAGCUUCGUCGUCACCUCCAGAAUUUACACUGGAAAGUCUCAGUUGAAUUUGAAGGUUACAGGAUGUGCAUCUGUCACUUACCUUGUCGACCAGUGAAACCAAACAUUAUUGGAGAACAGAUAACCAGUAAAAUGGGAGCCCAUUAUCAUUGUAUCAUUUGUUCAGCAACAAUCACCAGAAGAACUGAUAUGCUAGGACAUGUUAGGCGCCACAUGAAUAAAGGAGAGACUAAAUCUAGUUAUAUUGCAGCUUCCACUGCUAAACCACCUAAGGAAAUUUUGAAAGAGGCAGACACGGAUGUACAAGUUUGUCCCAACUAUUCUAUACCUCAGAAAACAGAUUCCUAUUUUAACCCCAAAAUGAAACUAAAUCGGCAGCUAAUAUUCUGUACAUUGGCUGCUUUGGCUGAGGAACGAAAACCUUUGGAAUGUCUAGAUGCUUUUGGAGCCACUGGGAUAAUGGGAUUACAGUGGGCAAAACAUCUUGGAAAUGCAGUCAAAGUUACAAUCAAUGACUUGAAUGAAAAUUCUGUGACACUGAUUCAGGAAAACUGCCAUUUAAACAAAUUGAAAGUGGUGGUGGACAGUAAGGAAAAGGAAAAGAGUGAUGAUAUUCUUGAAGAAGGAGAGAAAAAUCUUGGUAAUAUUAAGGUGACCAAAAUGGAUGCCAAUGUACUGAUGCAUUUGAGAUCUUUUGAUUUCAUACAUCUAGACCCUUUUGGAACAUCAGUGAAUUAUCUAGAUUCUGCAUUCAGAAAUAUAAGAAACCUUGGCAUAGUGUCAGUGACUUCUACAGAUAUCAGUUCUUUAUAUGCCAAGGCACAGCAUGUUGCCCGGCGUCACUACGGAUGUAACAUUGUCCGAACUGAAUAUUACAAGGAACUAGCAGCCAGAAUUGUUGUAGCUGCAGUGGCAAGAGCUGCAGCCCGAUGCAACAAAGGCAUAGAAGUACUGUUUGCAGUGGCUCUGGAACAUUUUGUGUUGGUAGUUGUGAGAGUUUUGAGGGGACCUACUUCAGCAGAUGAAACAGCCAAGAAGAUUCAAUACCUGAUCCAUUGUCAGUGGUGUGAAGAGAGAAUUUUUCAGAAGGAUGGUAAUAUGGUAGAAGAAAACCCAUAUAGACAGCUGCCUUGUAACUGUCAUGGAAGCAUGCCUGGAAAGACAGCAAUAGAACUUGGACCUCUGUGGUCAAGUUCCCUUUUCAAUACUGGAUUCCUCAAAAGAAUGCUAUUUGAAUCUCUUCACCAUGGUUUGGAUGACAUUCAGACCCUAAUAAAGACAUUAAUCUUUGAAUCAGAGUGUACGCCUCAAAGUCAGUUUUCAAUUCAUGCAUCUUCAAAUGUCAACAAGCAAGAAGAAAAUGGUGUAUUUAUUAAAACUACAGAUGACACCACAACAGAUAAUUACAUUGCACAAGGAAAGAGAAAAAGUAAUGAAAUGAUCACAAAUUUAGGCAAGAAGCAAAAGACUGAUGUCAGUACUGAACAUCCUCCCUUUUAUUACAACAUUCACAGACACAGCAUUAAAGGAAUGAAUAUGCCAAAGUUAAAAAAGUUUUUGUGCUAUUUAUCUCAAGCAGGCUUUCGAGUAAGCCGAACUCAUUUUGACCCAAUGGGUGUACGCACAGAUGCACCUCUGAUGCAGUUUAAAUCUAUCCUUUUAAAGUACAGCACCCCCACCUACACUGGAGGACAGUCAGAAAGCCAUGUCCAGUCAGCAUCUGAAGAUACAGUAACUGAAAGAGUUGAAAUGUCAGUGAAUGACAAAGCAGAAGCAAGUGGCUGCAGAAGAUGGUAAACGUAGAGAAGAAUUGGUUCUCAGGUGUCUGUAUAGAUGGCCUAAUAGUUCUCUAUACCAACUGUAGUUCUUUUUCUGUUCUUUCAAUUCAGUAGAGUAAAAAUAAAAAACAGUGUCAUUUUCAUUCAGAAACUGAGCAGUUUCUAACUUAGCUGGUUUGGGAGCUUUGCUUUCCAAGUUUUUUUUUGUUUUAAGGCAAACUUAAAAUUUUAAUGGAAACAUUUCAUAUGAAGCCAAGUCUCACUGAGAUCACCCUACUGCUUAAUAAUUCAGAAAAUUUUCACAUGCAAAGUGUUUGGAAUUUUAUGUAUGUUAUGAAAGCCAUCUUUUACAAUUCUUAAUCACAUCUCUGCCUAAACUGAUUCAUGAUGUUUAUGUUUUCCUGUUUGUAGUGUACAAAAUGAAGCUGAAGGCUCACAUGUUAAAAUGACCCUGAAUAGAAUAGGAAGAACAAUGUUCUUACAGGUCAUAAUGUAUUUCACAAUUAAAAAACUAAAAUAUGUACCCAUUUUUAAGAAAUCAUACUUCUCUCCACAUUGAUCUUUUCAUUUCUUACUAGCUUUUAAGAAAUUAAAUACUUGCCUGAGAUAGAAAUACUUUAUUUUUGUAACUUUAAGGUCUAAAUGACUAAACUUCAAAGUAAGAUUUUGUCAGAAUAAAUUGAGACCAUUAAUCUAAUAUAAUACUUGUUCAUGAGCACUGAAAUCCUGAAGAGGAGAGAUUUGGUUAUAAAUUAAAAAGGUUGGGUGAUCUUAAGUGCCUCAGUUAAUGCACGUACAGUAUUCAUUUGGUUGGUUGUACUACCUCUCAGAAGUAAAAUUUGUCACCUUAUGGAAUGAGAGUUUUUGGGUUUGGGGGUUGUUUUUUUGUUGUUGCUUGGUUUGGUAUUUUUGGUUUUGUGUGUAUUUGUAUAAAUUUUCUGUAUAAUUAGCCCAGGCUGAUGUAACUAUAAAAAUUAGUUGAAAAAAAAAAUAUUGUUUCCUUAAUGGAAUUCUCACUUCAUUUGAAUAUAAGAUUUUGGAUGAAAGGAUUUGGUAUAAAGUUUGGGUUUUUGUCUCAAGGAUUUGAUCCAUAUUUAUCCCUAAAUAUUUCUUAAGGGAUGUAACUUUUUAUAACCAUUAAGUGGGGGGAAGGGGGUGGAGGGGGUGGUAAUAAUUAUAACUGAAAGGUUUAAAUAUACUACCUAAGAAAAAAGUACUUCUGUGACAUAUACAAAAAAAUCUAGUGGAUAGGCAUUAGAUGAAUAGAGAAUAUUAAUUUUGCAGAAAUGAAGGAAAAUCUCUUCGUGCUAGUACAGCGUAUUCCCAAGAGAGUUUAUUUUCCUUUCUCCAAUUAAUGUGGUCAUAAAUUUCGGUAAAAUCAAGAAAUAGGUGAAGUGCAAGCUAGUUUCUAUAAUGACCAUUAAAAAAAUUCUGCUGUGUAAUUCUUGCCAGUUAAAAUUAUAACUUGCAAAUGAGCAGAAUAAAUGAGGUUUUUUUCAAUUAAAAAUUACUAUAAAUCCAGGAGGCAAACUAUUUUAGCACUCAGAUUAUCUGAUUUAAUACAUAUUAUUGAAUAUCAGUCUCAAAUUUUGCUAAAUGCUUAUCAGCAUGAAAUAUGUUGAUCAGUGAUGAGUUGGGCUUAAUGCAAAGAUCCUAAUUUAAUAAAGAAACCUGUAAAUUACUGUUACCUAAAAUAUAUGUGUAUAUUAAUUUCACAUAUAAAGGUAGAUUUUUCAAAGAAAAAUUUGGUAGGCGGUAGUUUAGAACUCUGAUCAGGUACUACAUCAACCAAAAGAGGAAAUACUUUAAAAAUUCCUUUUAGCAACCUGAGCAAUCUUAUUCUCGUAACAAUAGUAGUAAUUUGGGACAUUGCAAAUGUUUAUCAUGUUGUAAAGUAGCAUCAGUUGUAUCCUUUCAUUAAAACUUGAUAAACAAAA